UCCUCCUGCCUUGGCAUUCCAAAAUGUUGGGAUUACAGGCAUGAGCCACCGUGCCUGGCCUCCAGGAAAAAAAAACGUCUGGCUGCUGUAGGCAGAGUAAAUGGGUUGGAUAAUUUGUACUCCCCUGCAUUCCUAUUCCCUCAUUUUAAUGGUGUAGAAAGUAAGGUUGAGUGAAAGGGGGUGACUUACCCAAGGUUACAUAGUUAGAUACUGCCAGCCCUGGGCCUAGAACUCAUAUUUUUUAAUUAAAAGCUUUUCCCAAGCCCCACACCUCUGCUUUCCUUAUAAACCUGCACUGGCUUUUUUUCCAGAAAACUUCCAGGUGGCUUCUUACUACUUUCAGUGCUGUGAGUGCAAGGAGUACACAUGGAACACACAAACUCCCGAAAAAUGCAGUCCUCUGCCAGGCACAGUGGCUCAUGCCUGUAAUCCCAGCACUUUAGGAGGCUGAGACAUAUGAACAGGUAUUUAAAAUGCAAUGUGAUAUUCGUUGUACUGGAAGGAUGUUCAGGGUGCUGCGGGAACCCAGAAGAGGGACUAAUUAACUCAUCCCGGGGGAAAUUGAUCUUGCUGCUCAAAGGUGGAACAUUUGAACAGGUAUGAAAGGAUGAAUAGGAGUUUAUCUGAAAAGGAGAGGGGCAAGAAAGAGUAUUUCAGGAAGAGGAAACAGCAUUUUUCACAGACACAGAGUCAUGCAAAAGUCUGGUGUAUUCAAGAGAUAGCAGAGAUGUUGGGCAUGGCAAAAACACAGGUUGUAUGUUAGGCAAAGCUAAAGAUGAGAUUAGAGAGAGAUAAGGUCAAUUUACAAGGGGCAUUGAAUGCCAAGCUGAGGACUUUGGCUUUAAGGCCAAGGGAGCAGAGGAUGUGUGAUGAGGCCUUGUUUGACCUAUUCAGUUCUUUCUCUUUUUUCAUUCUGCUCGUGAGGCCAUGUUACAAUGACUGAUGUUUGGGCAUCUGGUACCCGGGAUGUCUUGUGGAAGUCGUUUUCAACAAUUAGAGCAGCAUUUCUGUCCUGCUGUAGAUGAGGAGGUCACCUCAGGGUGAGCCAAGUGGAAGAGAGGGACAGUAGCCUUAUUCCCCUGGAUGAUGUCACCUGUGGAGAGCAUCCUUCUCCACCUCUGGCCAUUGUUCUUGACAGGCAGGAGAAUAUGCAGGACAUUCCAGAUACAGUCCUGUCAUUAACACCCAUGGCUCUGCAAAAACUCAGAAAGUUUUUCUUUUCUUUUCUUUUCUUUUUUUUUUUGGUGGGGUGAGGGAGUAUUAAACUAUUAUUUUUCAUGAUUUUGUGGAUUUCUAUUUUCCUGGGAUGUAUCAGUUAGCUUUUACUGCAUAACAAGCCACCUCUAAACUUUGUGCUUAAAACAACUAAACUUUAUUUAUUUUAUGAUUCUACAGUUUGGCUGUUUGGGCUGGGAUUCUCUGGGUAAUUCUUCUGGUUUGGCCUGGGCUUAGCUAAUUAUAACUGUGUUCACUCUUGCACUGUAUUCAGCUAGUGGGUUAGUUGGGGCUGGCUGGUCUAUGAUGGCCUCAGGUGGGAUGCCUGAGACAACUGAGAACUUUCUCUGCAUGAUCUCUCAUCUUCCAGCAGUCUCAAUGCCAGGUUAGAUUUUUCACAUGGCACUCUUAAAGUUCUAAGAACAAGAGCAGAAUUAUAUAAGGCCACUGAGGUCUAGGCUUGGAAAACUUGUCACUUUUGCUGCAUUCUGUUGGCCAAAGAAAGUCACAAGGUGAGCUUAGAUUCAAAGGGCAAAGGGUCCUACCUCUUUUAAAAAUUAAAAACUCAUCACUGACCUGAAGCUCGUGGAGAGUCUUACCUUUUGAUGGUAGGAUUGCAAGGGUAUGGAUGCAGGGAGGGGAAGAAUUUGUGGCCAUUUUUUGAAUCUACCACUCAAACUAACUUUCGUCACCAGAGAGUUGGUAAUUGAGUUUAUUGCAUUACUGUGAAUAGGAUAUGAGGAAUCUUUUGAACUCCAAAGUUGACAUUCAUGGAGGACCAUGUGAUUUCUGAAGUCUUAUCUAAUUUAAUGUGCACAGCAACUCUUAUUUUCCCUAUUUUACAUAUGAAGAAACUGGGGUACAGGGCAAUUAAGUGAGAUUAAGUGUUUUGCCCAAGGUCAUUGGCUGGUAGGCCUGGUAUUUUGGACUUACAUUUGUCUGACUAUAAGUCUGGAGCAACUGCCAUCAUAUCAUUCUUUCGUAUUUUGAAGAGAUGAGACAGAGGAGAUUGUAGCGGUACUGCUGCAUUCACUGCCAUAGCCAACCCCUUUCCAGAUCACCCUCAUCCCUGGACACAGGUACCUUGCCCUACUCCAGAGGCUCAUUUUCUUGUUCCUAGUAGGUUGACUGCCCUUGCGGUGGGCCGGCAGAAUCACUGUGGUCUCCAGGGUGGGAGUCUUCUGCUGCUUUUAUAGUCCAGAAGCCCACUAUGCUGAAGAAUAUGUUAGAGACUGAUGUAUUUCUCUGGGGAGAGAUUGUAGGUCAAGCUGUUCAUAGGUAAAAUAUACAUAUAUAUGAUGCAUCUAACUUGGUCUAUGGGGAGAGAGCCCUCCAAAAGACCUCUGAGCCUCAGAGGCAGACUGACUGGUAUAUGCUGUACUAAGAGAAAAAUACCUCCUAGAUGAGCGGGCAGGGAGGCCUUGCCUUUCUCUGACUAAAGCCUUCUGGAGGCUUUAGCUUCGAGAUCUUCCAAGUCAUCCUGCUAUGUGGUAACCUUAAUGACCUGGAACUGUGCCCAGACUAAACUGACUCUGGAUCUUGGCUAGUGAUGGGAGCUGUGCUCUCAGGGAUGUGGAAUGAGGAAUGGGAGCAGCAAGAAGGCACCUGAUUGUCAGAACCAAAGCAGCGUUGGGCCUGUAGUAGCAUGGUUUAUGGGGCAGGGAGGAAGGUAGGACCAGGUAAAGACAAGAAUGUGAGGAGACCAGAUGGUCUGUAGGGAAGGCCCCAAUGGGAUGGUCAUGUUCAGGGUACCCACAUACUAAAUGCAGGCUAUGGCAUCAAGUGUAGUUCAUUUUGGCACACAUGGGUAUUGCCAUGUAUCUUGGUGUUGUGUAUUAGAAAGCCUUAUGUCCAGGCCUUAGUUAUAAUCAGCCAUGUUGCCCUGACUCUGCUAUCUUUCUUUCUUGCACAGAGCUCAUCUCCUGUCCUGGGUGUGAACGAGUAUAUCUUACCAGGGAUGUAACUGAACAUUUUUUUCUGCAUUGUGUUCCUACUGAGCAACCCAAGAUGGCCAGGAACUGCUCUGAGUGCAAGGAGAAGAGGGCAGCACAUAUCCUCUGCACCUACUGCAAUCGCUGGCUGUGCAGCUCUUGCACAGAGGAACACCGACACAGCCCUGUCCCCGGGGGCCCAUUCUUUCCUCGGGCCCAGAAGGGAUCUCCAGGAGUGAAUGGUGGUCCCGGAGACUUCACCUUGUAUUGUCCUCUACACACACAGGAAGUACUCAAGCUAUUCUGUGAGACAUGUGAUAUGCUCACUUGCCAUAGCUGCCUAGUGGUGGAACACAAAGAACACAGGUGCAGACAUGUUGAAGAAGUUUUGCAAAACCAGAGGAUGCUUCUGGAAGGUGUGACUACACAGGUGGCACAUAAGAAAUCCAGUCUACAGACAUCUGCAAAGCAAAUUGAGGACAGGAUUUUUGAAGUGAAGCAUCAGCAUAGGAAGGUGGAAAACCAGAUCAAAAUGGCCAAGAUGGUUCUGAUGAAUGAGCUGAACAAACAGGCCAAUGGGCUAAUAGAGGAAUUAGAGGGGAUUACUAAUGAGAGAAAGCGGAAGCUGGAACAGCAGUUACAGAGCAUCAUGGUUCUCAACCGUCAGUUUGAGCAUGUGCAGAAUUUCAUCAACUGGGCUGUCUGCAGCAAAACCAGUGUCCCUUUUCUUUUCAGCAAAGAGCUGAUUGUGUUUCAGAUGCAGCGAUUGCUGGAGACAAGUUGUAACACAGAUCCUGGCUCCCCUUGGAGUAUCAGAUUCACCUGGGAGCCUAACUUCUGGACCAAGCAGCUAGCUUCUCUUGGCUGCAUAACUACUGAAGGUGGACAAAUGUCCAGGGCAGAUGCUCCUGCUUAUGGAGGCUUACAGGGGUCAUCACCCUUUUAUCAAAGCCACCAGUCUCCAGUGGCUCAGCAAGAGGCUCUUAGCCACCCCUCACACAAGUUCCAGUCUCCAGCAGUGUGCUCCUCAUCUGUGUGCUGCUCCCACUGCUCCCCAGUCUCGCCUUCCCUCAAAGGCCAGGUCCCCCCACCCAGCAUACACCCAGCCCACAGCUUCAGGCAGCCCCCUGAGAUGGUGCCCCAGCAGCUGGGGUCUCUGCAGUGCUCUGCCCUGCUGCCCAGGGAGAAAGAGCUGGCCUGCAGCCCUCAUCCACCAAAGCUGCUGCAGCCCUGGCUGGAAACCCAGCCCCCCGUGGAGCAGGAGAGCACAUCCCAGCGGCUGGGGCAGCAGCUGACUUCCCAGCCCGUGUGCAUUGUCCCCCCACAGGAUGUUCAGCAAGGAGCCCAUGCCCAGCCCACCUUACAGACACCCUCUAUCCAAGUCCAGUUUGGCCACCACCAGAAGCUGAAGCUCAGUCACUUUCAGCAGCAGCCACAGCAGCAGCUACCACCUCCACCACCACCCCUCCCCCAUCCCCCACCUCCCCUUCCCCCUCCCCCACAGCAGCCACACCCACCUCUUCCUCCAUCCCAGCAUCUGGCUUCUAGUCAGCACGAGAGCCCUCCUGGCCCUGCCUGUUCUCAGAACAUGGACAUAAUGCAUCACAAGUUUGAGCUGGAGGAAAUGCAGAAGGACUUGGAGCUUCUUCUCCAGGCUCAACAGCCCAGCCUGCAACUGAGUCAGACCAAAUCUCCUCAGCAUCUUCAGCAAACCAUUGUGGGGCAGAUCAACUACAUCGUGAGGCAGCCAGCACCUGUCCAGUCCCAGAGCCAGGAGGAGACCCUGCAGGCUACAGAUGAGCCCCCAGCAUCUCAGGGCUCAAAGCCGGCUCUCCCUCUUGACAAGAAUACUGCUGCUGCCUUGCCCCAGGCGUCUGGGGAAGAAACCCCUCUCAGUGUCCCCCCAGUGGACAGCACCAUCCAGCACUCCUCUCCAAAUGUGGUGAGAAAGCACUCCACCUCGCUGAGCAUCAUGGGCUUUUCCAACACUCUGGAGAUGGAGUUGUCAUCUACCAGGUUGGAGAGGCCCCUAGAGCCACAGAUCCAGAGUGUGAGCAACCUGACAGCUGGUGCCCCCCAGGCAGUACCAAGCCUGCUGAGUGCUCCCCCCAAAAUGGUGUCCAGCCUGACAAGUGUUCAAAACCAGGCCAUGCCCAGCCUGACAACCAGUCACCUACAGACUGUGCCCAGCCUUGUGCAUAGCACAUUCCAGUCCAUGCCCAACCUGAUAAGUGACUCCCCUCAGGCUAUGGCAAGCCUGGCAAGUGAUCACCCUCAGGCUGGGCCCAGCCUAAUGUCUGGUCACACCCAGGCUGUGCCGAGUCUGGCAACUUGUCCUCUGCAGAGCAUCCCUCCAGUUUCUGACAUGCAGCCAGAAACUGGGUCCAGCUCCAGUUCUGGCCGAACUUCAGGGAGCCUGUGUCCCAGAGAUGGGGCUGAUCCCUCCCUGGAGAAUGCUCUGUGUAAGAUGGAAAGUGAGGAUUCCACUCGCUUCACUGACUUACUGGGACAAGGUCCCAUAGUCCCCGGUCUGGAUGCUCCCAAGGACUUGGCCAUCCCCUCAGAACUGGAGGAGCCAAUUAACCUCUCUGUGAAGAAACCUCCACUGGCGCCAGUGGUCAGCACGUCUACAGCUCUGCAGCAGUACCAGAACCCAAAAGAGUGUGAGAAUUUUGAACAAGGAGCCCUAGAGCUGGAUGCAAAAGAGAACCAGAGCAUCAGAGCCUUCAAUAGUGAGCAUAAGAUUCCCUAUGUGCGACUGGAGCGACUCAAGAUCUGUGCUGCCUCCUCAGGAGAGAUGCCUGUGUUCAAACUGAAGCCACAGAAGAAUGAUCAGGAUGGGAGCUUCCUGCUGAUCAUCGAGUGUGGCACUGAGUCCUCCAGCAUGUCCAUUAAGCGGCCACCAGAAGUGGAGGGCACAUCUCCUGAAGAACACAGACUCAUUCCUCGAACCCCAGGAGCCAAGAAGGGCCCCCCAGCCCCAAUAGAGAAUGAGGACUUCUGUGCUGUUUGCCUCAAUGGCGGAGAGUUACUGUGCUGUGACCGCUGCCCCAAAGUGUUCCACCUCUCCUGCCAUGUGCCAGCCUUGCUCAGCUUCCCAGGGGGAGAGUGGGUGUGUACCUUGUGCCGCAGCCUGACCCAGCCCGAGAUGGAGUACGACUGUGAGAAUGCCUGCUAUAACCAGCCUGGAAUGCGGGCAUCUCCUGGCCUAAGCAUGUAUGACCAGAAGAAGUGUGAGAAGCUGGUAUUGUCCUUGUGCUGCAAUAACCUCAGCCUGCCCUUCCAUGAACCUGUCAGCCCCCUGGCCCGGCAUUAUUACCAGAUUAUCAAGAGGCCCAUGGACCUGUCAAUCAUCCGGAGGAAGCUGCAAAAGAAGGACCCAGCUCACUAUACCACCCCAGAGGAGGUGGUAUCAGAUGUGCGCCUCAUGUUCUGGAACUGUGCUAAGUUCAAUUAUCCUGACUCCGAGGUUGCAGAGGCUGGCCGCUGCCUGGAAGUGUUCUUUGAGGGCUGGUUGAAGGAGAUCUACCCGGAGAAACGGUUUGCCCAGCCAAGGCAGGAGGACUCAGACUCCGAGGAGGUGUCUAGUGAGAGUGGAUGUUCCACUCCCCAGGGCUUCCCGUGGCCUCCCUACAUGCAGGAGGGCAUCCAACCCAAGAGGCGGCGACGACAUAUGGAGAAUGAAAGAGCAAAAAGAAUGUCAUUUCGCCUGGCCAACAGCAUCUCUCAGGUGUGAGAGCCAAAAGGAGACUGGGCACUCUGGCAGCUGUUGUCCCAUACUGUCGACCAUUCCUCCCCAUCUUGCAGCUUAUCCUCUUCAGAGUGUGGAUGGUAGAUGAGUCUUGUUGAACUGUGUAGUGCUCUUCUUUGCCAUUUGCAUCUACAGCAUUUAUUUGGGAGCCGUAGUACAUCCACUACAGAGAAGAUUUCAGUAAUAAACAGGAAAGAGGAAGGUAUUUAUUAUUACCAGAGUAAUCAGAUGUAUAGGCUCCACUUGACAAGACCACACCUGGUUAGGCUCGGGAAAACCUACUUUCCUUGGUGAAUUUUUUUCUGCCUGGGAAAGCAGACCCGUCUAACCUUUUAGUGUCCAGGGCUCAGGAGCCAUGUAUACAUCUGAACUCCUCCUGGGCUCAGAAGUGGGUAAAAGAAGGGAGAGAGGUUUAGACAUAUGGCAGGACUGUGAUCCCUGGCCCAGCACAGCCAAAGACUGUCACUGUUUGCCUUUGCUUGUCCUGUCUGGAUAGAGGCACCUGCCAUGUGCAGACUAGUGGAGGCUUCUAGAGGCCAUAGGUCUCAAUUUGUGCCUAUUUGGGUUCUAACGGUUUUCAGGGUAUUUGUUUUGCAUAGUCACUUUCCUGAUGUUGACAUAGGUGGCUGCUGUGAAAAUGCUGUGGAUGGUGUGACAUUCUUGACUGAGCUGGGUGGCUGUGGAGAGACCACUUAAAUCUUCUGGUUCAGAUUUCACUUACAGACUUAGUAAGAUGUCCACUUCAGAGCCCGCCCUCUGUGCUACUUACUCUGGGCUAAUCACACUUCUUUAGGGUGAGAACCUGCCUUCCUAGAAGUGACUGUUGGUGCUUGUCAGUGGCCAUACCCUUCAUCAUCCUCAUUCAGAGGUAUGGAUCGUGAGUUCUGCUUGUGAAUACUGUGAGACAGCUGCUGUCUGCUUCAGGUCCAGAGUUCCAUGGGUGGAGAGAGUAACCCACAACCAGCUCACUCCUCUGGGCCUCUCCUCCUGCUUAAAGAUUCUAGUUCUCAACCUCUCCAAGUUCAUGAGCCAAAGAUCAGAAGUGAGUCUUCUGACCAGCCCGCCUCCAGGCUGUCUACAGCCCCAAAAAAGCCAACACUUUUCUGGCAGCCCUUUUUGUUGGAGGUUAGAGAAGGCCUCAGGGACCAACAGGGGCCAGAUCUAGACAUUCCUGGGGGAAGUUUGUCUAAGGUGGACAGGGGGAAAAAUCAAGAGGCAAAAAGCCAGUGUCCUUUGGUGACCAUGAAGCAACCUCAGAGCCUUAGUUCUCCUAGAAUGCAGAGAGAAGCAUUCUGGAAGCCAUGGGAACAGGAGCUCGAGGCUGCAUCCUGAAUGCAUCUGCAUGGCCCUCGCAGGGUGUUUGUGAGGAUACUGGAGGUCAGGCUACCUCCCAAGCAAGGGCUUGGUUGAGAAGGAACCCAUUGCUCAUAUUGUUGGGGGAGCUAUGAACCUGACAUGUCAGUGGCCAGGACUGAGACAGCUCUCCCUGGUCCUGUCAUUGCAUGGCUAAUUUCAGGGGAGUCUGAGGUCAUGGCUUUAUUUUUGCUAACAGAUGAAGUUCAAGGAUGUUCUUGUUUGUAGGGCCUUUGCUAAUGAGCAGUUUUUUAAUUAGAAAACAUUUCUUCUCUCUUUGUGAGUUGAUGGUAUUGCUCAUUUCCUUCUCUACCCAACCUGAGAGAUCAUCUUCACUUUAAAGCAAACCAUGCCCCUUGGCUUGCCAUUCUUUCAGCAGCACAUGCCACGUUCUAAGCAGAUGGGCUUCCGUGAUCCCGUUUUCUAGUUUGGGGUAACUGAGUCUUGAAUGCUUUACUAGUCCGGCAAUCUUUGGACUUAGGCUUCUGCCCUUUGAGACUCACAUGACUUUCUGGUUUGGGGUCUGGUCAUUUCCCUUUCAAUUUUUGAAUCUCCUUCUCUGUUCAGUUGGCUUGGCAAAGUACCCUCUGUUCUCAUGUCACUAAUUCCUGCUCUAGGUCAUCUUUCCUUUGUGCAGCCCACAUUCCCACCAUCCUGUGAACUUUGUUGUACUUGGUGUUGGGCAACUGGUGAGUGUUGUGACAGGCUCAGACCUGAUCCUUCCUCAGGAGCAAUUGGAGACCACAAAUUUAAAGCAGAAAUACCUGUUAAAAGCUUGGCUUUCCUUAUAUGAGUGAGGCUCCCAGCUUGGGUGUGGCCUCCUGGGCUCACGGAUCAGCUUGCUGGGCCAGAGGGGGUCUUAGUAAUGUGCUAGAGAGACACAUGCUCCCUUCUCAUCGUAGAGAGCCUGCAUGCUGAGAGGCUCCCUUUACACACCUGCCUCUCGCUGGCUUUUCCUUUAGACCUAGCCACCAGUGUUUUGAAUCAUGGUUUUGUUUUGUUUUUGCAUGCAAAAACCAGAACAUGACUUAGAAAUUAAAAAAAAAAAAAUCCUACUAGCCAAGUGACUGCCUGCAGAGGCUCUUCAUUAACAUUUGGGCUGAUCCUGCUUUUGACUUAUUCCCAUAAUGGCCCAGUUUUGAAGUCAGCCAAGUCCUUUUGUCCUUGACAACAUCAUGCAGUGGAAAUACGGUGAGUUCUAGAUUCUUAUGGGACAGCAUGCAGCCCUAGAGGAAAAAUUGACUUCUUGGGUAUGCUGAGAAAUAAGACAGUAAAAUGGCUUCAGUUGAUGCAAGGGGAUUUUAGUUAAAAAUUGGUUCAGGAUUUUUAAAUUUUAUUUUAUUUUUUGGCUGGGCGCGGUGGCUCACGCCUGUAAUCCCAGCACUUUGGGAGGCUGAGGUGGGUGGAUCACCUAAGGACAGCAGUUCGAGACCAGCCUGGCCAACAUAGUGAAACCCUGUCUCUACUAAAAAUACAAAUAUCAGCCAGGUGUGAUGGCACAUGCCUGUAAUCCCAGCUACUUGGGAGGCUGAGGCAGGAGAAUUGCUUGAAUCCGGGAGGUGGAGGUUGCAGUGAGCUGAGAUCAUGCCAUUGCAUUCCAGCCUGGGCAACAGAACGAGACUCCGUCUCAAAAAAAAAAAAAUUGGUUCAGGAUGAACUUGCAGAGCACUCUUCCACAGAACAUGGUUAGGUUAGCCCUGCCUGACUUCUAGCAAUUGCUAACUAUACACCUUGCCUGCCUCUAGGACCCCUACCUGAGUGGCAACCAUACCUUCCAUAUGCUCUGUUCCAUGGCAGUCCCUGCCAUCCCCCACCAGCGGACUCUGGCUCCCUCCCUGUACCCAUUUCUAGCAACAGCUCCUUGCCUGGCUGCUAAGACGGAGGCGCCUCCUUGUUUGUUCCUGGGCUCUGUUCUGCUCCCUCUCUCACUCCAUGGAGUCACUUAUAGUCUUCCUUUCUGAACGCCAGAAUUGAGCCUUUGCUCCUUCUGGAUCACCCCUUCCUGGGCUUCUUCUCCAUCCCUCAGUACUGCUAAAAUUGCCCUGCUCCUUUAGUCCAUUUCCAUGACCUCAGCCCUCUCUCUCCUCUCCUUGUCUUUUAACUUUCUCCUGGACUUCUUCCUCUCCCCAGCAUGAACCCAGAGCCUAUCACACACUGAUGUUUUUGUCAGCAUCCUGAACUUUCUCAUGCCCUUCAACUUUAUUUAUUUAUUUAUUUAUUUAUUUUUUAUUUUUUGAGAGAGAGAGUCUCACUCUGUCAUGCAGGCUGGAGUGCAGUGGUAUGAUGUCGGCUCAUUGCAACCUCUGCCUUCUGGGCUCAGGUGAUCCUCCCAUCUCAGCCUCCUGAGUAGCUGGGACUACAGGUGCAUGCCACCAUGCCUGGCUAAUUUUUCUACUUUAGGUAGAGAUGGAGUUUCGCCAUGUUGCUCAAGCUGGUAUCAACACUCCUGGGCUCAAGCAGUCUGCUUCCCUUGGCCUCCCAAAGUGCUGGGAUUACAGGCGUGAGCCACUGCGCCAGGCGUAUCCCCUUCAAUUUUGCUGAAACUAUCAGCCAUUCUCCAUUUUCGGCAUCAUCAUAUUUGCUGCUUCCACCUCCUGGGCUGCUAUGCAUGACAGAUUCACAGUUGGCAGCCUCAGUUGAGCUCUCAGUGUUGACUGGAAAUUCUUUAACUUGUUGUGAUCCCUUUUUUUUUCCCCACCCAUGCCUCCAUCUUUGUCCUCCACAAAUGACUGAGCUCACUGUCUACUUCACAGAAGACAGCCCCUAAAGCAAGAGCUUCCUUGCCUGCUGUUCCUCUCUCCCCUCUCAUUCAUCUGUGUCUGUAACUCUCCCCAACCCCUCCAUUCUUGCUCCUAUUUAAUUCUCUAUAUCUUGAAUCCUGUUGUAUGUCCUCCAAGACUGCUCCCUCGCUUACUCCACUGCUCCCACUCCCUGGAGUCUCCAGCCUCUGUCUCCACUGGUUACCUCCACACAGCCUGCAAACAAGUUCUCCACAAGAUUAAAACAGCAUUUCUCAGAGUCUGUUACCCCUUACACAUUUUCCUUGUUAACCAAGUUACUUUUAAAAAGAUCCUUUUUAAACUGAUUCUUCCUCAGCUGUUCUUCAGCCCUCUAUACUUUUUCAUAAAAGUCACCAGUGACUGCCCAGUUGCCAAAUAGAAUGAAUACCUUUCAGUGCUCAGCUGUCUUGACCUCUCCGCAGCAUUUCACACCACCCACCAACCCUCAGUGAAACAACCUCCUCCCUUAGCUUUUAUGACACCACAAGUCUCUGGAUUCUCAGAGAAUCCAGAAAAACAAGUCUCUGGAUUCUCUCCUCUUACCUCUCAGCCCACACAGGCUGAGCUGUCCUUGAAACCUAGAUGGGGGAAAUGUCUGUGGCUGUCUGUGGUCUCUUCUUUUCAGGAGUUGGGUAGGGAGGAAGAAUCACAGCUGCUCCUGCUUCCUCUGUCUGUCUCUCUAUUUCCUGAGUCCCUUCCUUUUCCUGAACUCAGUUCUCCUCAUGCCAACCAUGUUUAUGAGCUCCUGCUGGGAGGACAGCAUCUGUGAGUCCUUCCCUCUGUCUCUCCCAGACAACACAGAGGUUUUAGCCUGUUUGCUAAGAGACCCCAUCUAAGUCAGCCCAAGGGUGUGGAUUAGGUUUUACAGCAUCCAGGCCGCAGUCUGGCUAAACUGGAUUACCAGGCUGGUGGGCAGCUCCUCACCAUGAUCCUGCACCAGUUAGAGCCUGCUGUAGUUGGGAAGGAGCCUGGGAUUGUGGUAAGAUGUGUUUCCGUGCAUGUCAGUGCUGCUAACCAGGAGGAGAACCUGGCAGGGUGGGUGCCUGCUGCUGAUAACAUUCGGAUGGAGGGAGACUAGGGAGCGCGGUGGCUGCUCCCUUGCUGGGGCUCAGCUGGAGUCAGCAUGACUCCUUAUAUCAGGGCCUUUCCCACCUGUGCUGAUCACCACCACCUGCUUGCUCCAGUUGUUUCUGGAGUUGGAGGCAGCUAUUGGUUGCUUUCUUGGAGGUAAGGAGGUAUAUACUAGAAAGAUAUCUGAUUUGAGAGUCUGAACACCAAAAUUUUUGGCUCUUUCCAUUAUGAGCUGUGUAACCUUGGAUACAGUUUCCUCAUCUAUAAAGUUGUGGUGGGAGAAUGGCUGAGAACAGUGAUCUCUCAGCUCUCCAGCUGUAAAGAUGUUAAUUAUGAUUUUAACUCUCAAGAUCAGGCCACAUAAGGAACAGGGGAAUUCCAGGGGUGGGACACAGCUGGGGGAGUCCAGACCAGGGCAGGGAAAGGAGACUCACAAGCCAAACAGAGCUGCUUUGGGGAAAGUUCUUAUCAGCUGGUGCUGCUUCCUGAGCCAUAUGCCCAUUCCUCAAGCUGUACCCCUUUCUUGGCUAUGUAGGAUGAGUUCCUCCUAGGCCCUUGUUAGGAGUGGCUAUUGGAUUCUAAGCGGUUGGGGCAUGAGGGAGGAUAUUUUAAAGGGAAGUAUAGCUGAUUUUAAAAGAACCUAUACAUUCAAGAACAAAUAAAAAACAGCACUUUUCUUUACCAA